AAAAAAGUGUUUCUCCAGGACGAAGAUGGCGGCAACUUAGCCCGCGGACUGAAGAUGACUGUGGCUCUCGGGAGGCCCAGCCCAGGCGAUUCGGCCCGGAGCUCCGCGGGAGGCGGCGUCAGCAGUCGGAGCCCCGGCGGCGGCGCCCGCGGGCGGCCCUGCGGCAGCGGCGGCGGCGGCGGCGGCGGCGGCAGCACUUAGAGCGCGGGGUGGGGGGUGGGGGGGAGGGAGCGCCCCGCCGGAGGCAGCCCAGGCUCCGGACUCUGGGAGAGCCAGCGCGGAGCAGGAGCGGGAGGCGGAGGAGAAGAAGAAGGAGAAGGAAAGGAAGGAGGAGGAAGAGGAGGAGAAGAAGAGGAGGAGGAGGAGGAGGAGGGGAGGCGCUCCGGGCGCCGUCAGUGGGCAGCGGAGGCGCGGCAUGCCCCUGGCAGGGGAGAGCGGGCUGGGCUCCGCGGGGCCAUGGGGACCCGCGCGCUGACAAUGCCUGGGUGACCGGAGCCGCGCCAGCCACCCUGUCACCUCCACCAUCGCCCCCUGCACCCAGCCUCGCCGCCGGCCACCAGCACCAGCCUCCUCCGUCUCUCUCUCUCUCUCUCUCUCCAUUAUUGUUUCCCACUCUACAGAGGAUGGGGUCGGCUGAUGAUUAGGAAGCAAGUCAGACCUUCCUUCAAAGCCUGGUAAUAUUUAUGUAGGCAAAAGAGACAGAGAGAGAUAAAAGAGAGGGAGAGGGAGAGAGAGAGAGAGGAGAGAGGGAGAGGGGAAGAGAGAGAAAGAGAGAGAGGAGAGAGAAGAAACGGGAGGAGGGGAUAAGGAAAUUAAACCCUUUAAGUCAAUGCAUAUUGUGGUGACACCGGCACAGGCGCCCUCACGGUGGAGUCGGCCAGGGCUGUGCGUUCCCAAAAUAUGACCAGGGGUGCUUGGAUGUGUCGGCAGUAUGACGACGGCUUAAAAAUCUGGUUGGCAGCACCCCGAGAGAACGAGAAACCGUUCAUCGAUUCCGAGAGGGCUCAGAAAUGGCGACUGUCUCUGGCAUCUCUCUUGUUUUUCACAGUCCUGCUCUCUGAUCACUUGUGGUUCUGCGCCGAGGCCAAGCUGACCCGGGCCCGGGACAAGGAGCACCAGCAGCAGCAGCGGCAGCAGCAGCAGCAGCAGCAGCAGCAGAGGCAGCGGCAGCAGCAGCAGCAGCAGCGGCGGCAGCAGGAGCCCUCCUGGCCCGCGCUCCUGGCGAGCAUGGGGGAGUCCUCGCCCGCCGCCCAGGCACACAGACUCCUCUCCGCCUCCUCGUCCCCCACCCUGCCCCCCUCCCCGGGAGACGGCGGCGGCGGCGGCGGCAAGGGCAACCGAGGCAAAGACGACCGGGGCAAGGCUCUUUUUCUAGGAAACUCUGCCAAGCCCGUGUGGCGCCUGGAGACUUGUUACCCCCAGGGCGCGUCCUCGGGCCAGUGCUUCACGGUGGAGAAUGCGGACGCGGUGUGCGCCAGGAACUGGAGUCGGGGGGCGGCCGGGGGGGACGGGCAGGAGGUGAGGAGCAAGCAUCCCACUCCGCUCUGGAACUUGUCGGAUUUUUACCUUUCGUUUUGUAAUUCCUACACACUUUGGGAGUUGUUCUCGGGGUUGUCCAGUCCCAACACUUUGAACUGCAGUCUGGAUGUGGUGCUCAAGGAAGGCGGCGAGAUGACCACUUGCAGGCAGUGCGUCGAGGCUUACCAGGACUAUGACCACCAUGCUCAGGAGAAAUACGAAGAGUUUGAAAGCGUGCUCCACAAAUAUUUACAGUCGGAGGAGUACUCGGUGAAAUCCUGUCCUGAAGACUGUAAGAUUGUCUACAAAGCCUGGCUCUGUUCCCAGUAUUUUGAAGUCACACAGUUUAACUGCAGAAAGACAAUUCCUUGCAAGCAAUACUGUUUGGAGGUUCAGACGAGGUGUCCAUUUAUAUUGCCCGACAAUGAUGAAGUCAUCUACGGAGGCCUCUCCAGUUUCAUCUGUACAGGGCUUUAUGAAACCUUUCUAACCAAUGAUGAACCAGAAUGCUGUGACGUCAGGAGAGAAGAAAAAUCAAAUAACCCAUCCAAAGGGACCGUAGAGAAAAGUGGCUCCUGUCACAGGACAUCGCUCACAGUGUCAUCAGCAACAAGACUGUGCAACAGCAGACUCAAGCUGUGUGUUCUUGUACUGAUUCUCUUACACACAGUGCUCACAGCCUCGGCAGCACAGAACACAGCCGGACUGAGCUUUGGAGGCAUCAACACGCUGGAAGAAAACUCAACCAAUGAGGAGUAACGGAAGGACGAGUGUCACCACAGCAGCAGCUGGCCCGCCGUGAAAAAUGGCAACUGCUGUCUCAUGUAACAGAAACUGGGUGCUUUUACCCUCGAAUUACUUAUUGCAAGGCCUUUAGGGUAAAAUUUAAACAGAUGGGCCUGAAUCCAAACAAGGACACAACCACAGCUUUUUAUUGACUAAAAGGCUGGAAAGUGACUUUAAAUUUCUCACACCAUUUUAUACACUGUGUUUUAAUGUUUGGAGGUUUUAUUUGCUUUCGUUUUGGUUUGGGUUUAUUUGUUUGUUUAUUUUUUGCACUUGUUAAUACAGGAUUUAUUUUGGGGGAUGGUUUCUCAGAGGUAAACUAAGUCUUUUCACUGUCUCUAUCUCUCUAUAUAUUUCUAGUCAUUGUGUGUGUUCAUCAGAUAGUUCUGUCUUUAUGUCCUGUCAGCUUCUAUUAGAGGAAUGAUUGCUAUGACCUCAUGGUAUAGCAAAAAACAACAACAAAAAAAGAAUAAAAAAUAAAAAAGACAAAAAAAAGAAAACAACAAAAAAAUAAAAAUAAAAAAAAUCCCUAAGUCUCCCUUCUACCCACAGAACCAACAACACCCUUCCCGGCCUUUCCUUUCCCUCGCCCUCUUCUCGUCCCCUAAGCAAACAACAUCCGCUUGCUUCUGUCUGUGUAACCACAGUGAAUGGGUGUGCACGCUUGGUGGGCCUCUGAGCCCCUGUUGCACAAACCAGAAACAGAGCGGAGCCAAGGGGGCCUGACAAGAGUUCCUUUUUAGCUGAACAAACAAGUGCUCUCCAUAAUAGGUGGAAUCAGACAGUUAACACAUUUUUAUGUUGAAAACAAAAUAAAAGGAAAAAAUUAAAAAAAACUAUCAUGAACUGUAUUGCUCCAGUUCCCAUCCCCAAGUGGCCCAGCCCUUUCUUGCUGGUCCAGUUGGACAGGAGCAGCUAUCUAGAAUCAGGAUGCGGGGAGUGAGGAAGUUUUUCUUUUGACAAUGAAGGUGGGCUUUCAUUGUGAUUUUUGUUCUGUUGCAGUAAUAUAGGAGCACAUUUUGGCCAUUGUAAUUACAGGGAACAAACAAAGGGAUUGCGGACACAUAUCUGGACUUCUUUUCCUCCCUUAUUGUUGUGGAAGAGACACUAGAAAUGCUCAAACACCUGCAAUAUACAGAAUAUACACAAUUUUAUUCCAGUAUUUCCCUAACAUAUGGUUUAAAAUUAUUCCAGGUAUACAGUGUAUGCAAUUCUGCAUUAUCACAGAGGAACAACUUCUUUUUUAAAAAAUAAAUAGGUCAGCCAUUUUUAUUAACGUGCAAAAACUUUAUCACUCUAACAUGCUCUAGGUAGUUGAGGAAAAGAGGUCUGAUCACUGUUUGUAUUUUAUUUUCUUUGUGGGAACAUUUCACCUGCUGAGUGUACAUGAAUUUGCUUUCUAUAAAAGGCUUUUAUGAGUUUACAGUAGAAUCAGUGGAAGGAAGAGUUAAUAAGGGCUGUUUUUAAAAAAACAAACAAACAAACAAAACAAAUAAUUAAAAAAAAAAUUUUACAUUCCUUCCUAUUCUCUAACUACACUUGGGAAGUGCACUUCAGAUAAGUUUGCAGUGUGACUGAGAGAUGAAGGAAAUCCAUAGAAAAGGUCCUCUUAGUGAACAAAAUUUAGUUAUUAACUUUAUAGCUAUGAAAUUUCCCCGGGCAUUUGUUUUUGUUCAAACAGACUUUAACCUCUGCAUCAUACUUAACCCUGCGACAUGCGUACAGUAUGCAUAUUUUGUUUUGAAAAAAAAUGUUUCGUUCCAGUCUGUUAAGAAUAUUCAAAAAUAAUAAAGGUAUUGCUUAAUAAAAUUGCUAGAAUUGUUUAGCAGUACAUGCACAAUAUUUUACUAGAUUCUUUGUUUUAAUAGUGUUUUGUUGAGACUGAAAAUCUUAAAAUGGUCUGCGCAAAUACAAAAAAAAAGAAAACACCAAAAAUGCAAAAUUCUCCCGUUUUUGUUCCUUUUUUAAAAUUUUUUUUUCUGCAAAUGCAAAUACAUUCACAUGUGGACAGAUACAUACACAUAGGCAUCAUAUUUUAGUGUAUGGAAACAUGGUGCUUUUCUGGGGACACAAGCUGAGGAAGUGAAUGGCUCGGGGGAGACACAUUAAUUGCAUGGAAUUGUUGACUGUGAAACACUUGUAGAAAUGAGCACUUUGGUAUCCCAACCAAUGGUGGAAUACAGAUUUCAAUGGCGCUGGGGGGACGAGAAGCAGAGGAAUUGAGGCUGCAAGUGAUUCCUGAGGAAGAGCUCACAGGGUGAUUUUAUUCAGAUGACCUCUAAGGGAAUGGCUAGGAAGGAGUCUGUUCUGACCUUUAUCUACCUCUGCUGUGGUAAGGCCACUCCAUGUGCCAUCUCACCAUCUCUUCAGCGUUCCUCAUGCUGCUUCUCCCCGUGCCAUAGGCGUUUCCAUUCUUGCAGGAAAAUGACAAUGCAAGUGCAAAUUCCACUCACUUUUAUUGGUAUGACAAUAAAUUAUUCUUUCUAAACACUUAGCAAAAUGACGAAAAGCAGUAUUCCUUAAAAUAUAGGUUUUCAUUUUCUCAAUAUAUUUUGAACUGACUAAAGUUCUUUACAAAGACAAGAGGAUCAGAAGGUUCCACUUACCCGUGUUUUAGCGUUUGUUUGGAGAUAAUGCCAACCAAAAGGUGGAAAACUAAAACCACCAUUGCUUUACAUAAGAGGUACACACUGCCCCCCACCCCCCAAAAAAAAACACAGCUUUGAAAGUUGGGAGAAACACUGCAGUCUUCAUUGUAAAUAUAAAGUGAUAAUUUAGGUGAGGAAGGAACGGUAAGGAGGGAAGGGGAAUGAGUCCUUUCUCCCCAUCAAGUCAGCCAGCAUUGGAAUAGUCUCUAAUUCUGGCGGAAUAUUUUCUUUGUCAUGUUCAUCUAUUCUUAUUACAGGAGAAUGAUUUCAGUGCCUAGUAUUUAUUAGUGUAAGUGUGUAACCACUUUCCCGCAAUAUUUCCACUGGACAUGUUGAAGCAAAGCAGCUUCUUCUGGGGUCAGGCAGAGGAUCCAAAUAGGCAACGACUCCUUUCCCAAGCUCAGAAACAAUCACUGAUGAUGCAGAUUUCACUACAUCCGUUGAUUCUUUGUAGUAGUUUUCCUGGCACACACUUGAGCAUGCUUAAGGUUGUGCAUAUGUUCAUUUUGAACAAAUAAGUUCAGCCCCUGCUCCUUUGUAAUCAUCAUCUUGUUUAGUUUUUCCUGUAGAGGAUGUCUACCGUAUACUGGCUAAUGAACUACAAUAUUAAAAUAAUUAUUUCUGCAAGCAAGUUGAAAACCAAGAAAACAAUAUUUGUUUCAUAAAUGUAUGGCAUAGAUUUCCCUGUUUAUUAUUCUUUUUAUCUGCAAUAGAGAAAUUUCAGUUUCUGGAAUAUGUUGGUACUGCUAAGCUAAAUGGCAAAUAACAUAGAGUUCAAUGUCAUUCUUUAUUGCAUUUACAUUUGGUGAUACGUUAUAUUGAACUUUUCUUGCAUUAAAAAGAUAGUAUUUUUCCCCUCUCUCACAAGGCAGUAAGUGAAAGUUGUUCUUUUAAAUGGCAUCAUUACAAAAAGUAAUUUGGUUUCUUACCAAUAAAUUGGUACCUUAGGUACUAGAACCUGUAGUCAUUAAAACAAAAGAAAAUAGGCAGAUAGCAGAAACAAAAGAAUGACAGGAAAGAAGGAAGGAAAGAGGGGAGUGAGGGAGGGAGGGAAGAAGGGAGGGAUAGAGUCGGGGAAUGAGGGGGAAAGGAGGUUUCAUAUGAAUGAAUAAGUACAUACUUUUUUCCGGGGGAAAAAAACAUAAAUGAAAUAAGCAAUUGGAUGCCAGACCCAUGUGCCAAAUACCUGAAUUGGCAUAUGGUAUUUGAUAUCUGAACAACAUCAAAAACGUUAACCAGUCUGAAGCAUGAUUUACAUUCUUUCUCAGUAACAAAGACAUUUACAAUUUUCCUGCUACUCAAAGCAUUAAAUCAACACAGAACUGAAAGCUGCAUUUUGUUUUAUUUAUUUAGAACUGCAGUCAGGUAUUUAAUUUCUUUUCUGUGUGUUUGUUUGUUUUUUGAGAUGGCAUCUUGCUCUGUUGCUCAAGCUGGAAUGCAGCGGCAAGAUCUCUGCUCACUGCAACCUCCACUUCCUGGGUUCAAGCGAUUCUCCUGCCUCAAGCCUCUCGAGUAGCUGGGACUACAGGCUUGUGCCACCACGCCUGGCUAAUUUGUGUAUUUUUAGUAGAGACGUGGUGUCGCCAUGUUGGCCAGGCUAGUCUUGAACUCCUGACCUUGGGAGAUCCGCCGAUUAGGCCUCCCAAAGUGUUGGGAUUACAGGCGUGAGAUACCACACCCAGCCAGGUAUUUAAUUUCAUAAGUGUGCAUAUGCAUAUAUGAGGCGUUAGGGUUAUAUACUAUGGCAUAUCUUUAGAGAGAUAUAAAGAUAUAUAUACAUACACACACACACACACACACACACACACACACACAUCGCUUGCAAAUAAAACUUCAACCAAAACAUUAUGUAGUCCAUAACAGCACAUGUAUACCAUAAUGAUGAAUGAUCCUACUUGUUUGUCAAAGUUAGAGCAGCAUGGUCAUUUAAAAACCAUAUCUACUUUGACAAGGGAAACAGACUCUCAAAAUAUCUCCAUUAAUGAAUAAAUCACAAUUUUGAAACAGGCAGAAUCUCCAUCUUCCAAGCUUUAACAAUGUUUAUAAAAAACCUAAUAUAGCAGGUAGGUAUUGGGUGACAAUGAAUAAAAAGACUUUCAGUGGGGGGGAAGGAAAAUAACUAAGUAUAGUUUUCAAGCAAUGUCUUCAUGACAUUUAUAAGAACUAUCAAACAGCUACAAAUUCUAGAAAUUCUCCAAAUAAUGAGAAAAUGUAUAGAUAAUCUUCUUAGCCUUGGAAUAAAACUUAAGGCAUGAAACAAAAUAUGAACUAUGGUUUUUAUUCUUGAGAUACUGUACUUCAGGGCUAUGUUUACCACAGACAAGACAUUCAGAUUAAACUCAGAAGAAAAUCACCUGGUUAUUUUGUCCUGGGUCACACAGGUAGGUAAUGCAAAUGAUGGAACUCAAGCAUCUUCUGAUUACAAAUUACACAAGCUGGCUCCGAGGCACAGUGGGAUCCCUAGGUCUCAGACACACUUGAAGAGUUGAAUGGAUUUUCUUCAUACUCCAAGAUAUUUGUAGAAUCACUCAAUCUUAAAUGAAAAAAUCAAAAUGAUCAGGAAGAUCUAGCGAAUGUCUCAGAGUUCGUUUGUCAUGUUACAUUUUGUUCCAUGACUUUGCUGUGUUAUUCAAUAUUUUGGAGGUAAAGGAGAAGAGGGUCUAUGGGAAUAUUUUAAUAAAAUAUAGAUUUUUAAUUUUUAUUUUUAAUGUGGAGAAAAGGCACAGGAUCUUAGGGCAAAGCCAUGGUUUAGGGAUGAGCUUUGGCUCCAGGUGACACAGGGAGGUCAAUGAUGUAUUUGUACGUGACACCUCAUGCAAGAAGAAUACUUCGUGGCAACAUUGGAGGCUUAAAAGAGAUAAGUAAUAUAAAUGUGCCUGGACAAAACAGGUGCUCAGUAGUAGUUAGUUAUCAUGACUAUUCAUUCACAAAGUGAAACUGGAUUGGCUUGCUCAUAGGGACUGCUCCUGGAAGUUGUUCAGAGUUUCUGAAUUUCUUUGGCUUAUCUCUUAAUUACAUUUUUUUUUUAACAACACCUCACAUCCUUAAGCUAGCAGACUGACCAUCAAUAGAUUUUCAAUACAGUUUGAAAGUCUUAACAUAUAUUACAGAACUAAAGUGAGCUCUGAUGACUUUUAAUAUAAACAGCAUUGGCUAUUUUCGAUUUCCACUCCCAAAAGGCUACUACUGACAAGCAAAAGUUAAAGGCAUCUACACAAAUUGAAGUGGUUCUACAAGCAAGUGUAAAUUGAUCAACAGUGGUAGUAGAAAUAAUGAUGCAACUUCAAAGUGGUUGUUUAAGGCACUCAUAGAUCAAAAAAUAUAUAUAAAUAUUUGAUGCCUCUGAAUUCCUUAAAAAAACUAUAGUAAUUUUAAACAUGAAAAUGUUUAAAUUGGAACAUUUAUUAUGAAAAUUAAUUAAACUGAAUUAAUAUAUAUUUUAAUUAACACUAUAAUUAUUAUAGAAUGAAAUAACAGUGAAAAAGUUAGAAAACCUGUUCAGUUUUUGAUAAAGUAUAUGGAAAUAGAUUAAGCAGGGCUCUUGAGUAAAUUAUUUCAUUGAUUUGUAUCUAUUUAGGUAGGUGAGAGUUGCAUAGAAUCAGUGGCGAGAAGGAUCAGUGAAAUAAAUUUACAACUUCAGUGAAGACCAGGUAAUGAGCAUUGAUCUAUGAAUACAGACUUUCUUCAGUGACUAUUUCCCCUAAAACUCCCAGCUCACCGCAGCACUGCUGCUUCAAGAUUCCAGUUAUUGGCGUGCUAGCCAAGUAGAAGGUCAUUUUUACCGAAACGCAAAUUUCAACUUAUGGCCAUUUUCUACUGACCAUUUCACUGCAAAAUGGAUAAAACAAUAGGAAAUAUAAACUACAGCAAAAGUUAAAGCUCUAUAUGGACGUUAAAAGAAAACCUCUUGCUUUCUUUUUCUUCCUUUUUCUCUUGUUUUCUUUUUCUACCUUUUUCUGCAUAUGGCAUUUAUUUUCAUAUCAUGAUAAGCAUUCUCAUGUUUGCACUUAAUUUUCCUUAUUUCUAUUUUUCUUAGAUUUGUUGAUGUUGUGUGGCAUAUUAAAAGUAGGAAGGACUGUAUAAACUCAUGUAUUAUUUUUAAAUUGUUUUUCUGAAUGUACUCAAGUACUUUUUUAUGUGAAUAUGAACACGGAAUAAAAGUACUAAAACCAGUUAAUUAUGAGAGACUAAGAAUGUGGAAAGGAACAUUCCGGAGUAUAUUAGUAGCUAAAGAAAUGCCUUGGAUCUUAAAUUUCAACUUCUAAAAUUAUUAAAAUACAAAUAUUAAAAAGAUAUAGAGGCCACUGCUAAA